ACUCCCACCCCGGCAGCCCCUGUGCGUGGAAACCCAGCCAAGGUCUGAUGAUGGAGGAGCCUUGGCCCUGGCUGUCCCAGGGGAGGAGGUGAAAUUCCUCAGCUCUCCACCAAGAUUGGCCACAAAAGCCUGAUCCCCUGGAACACAGCAGGCCUCACAUAGACGGUCAGCCAUUGGAUCAUAGGAACUGCCCUGGCCUGACUCACCCAAUAUGGAGGAGGUGCCUGGGGAUGCCCUGUGUGAACACUUUGAGGCCAACAUACUUACCCAGAACCGCUGUCAAAACUGCUUCCACCCUGAGGAGGCCCAUGGAGCAAGAUACCAGGAGCUCAGGAGCCCUUCAGGUGCUGAGGUGCCCUACUGCGACCUGCCUCGAUGUCCACCUGCCCCUGAGGACCCACUCAGCGCCUCAACCUCCGGCUGCCAGUCUGUGGUGGACCCAGGCCUCAGGCCAGGGCCCAAGAGGGGCCCAUCCCCCUCAGCAGGGCUCCCAGAAGAGGGUCCCACAGCUGCCCCCAGGAGCAGGAGCCGGGAGCUUGAGGCAGUACCCUAUCUGGAGGGCCUGACCACUUCCUUGUGUGGCAGCUGCAACGAGGACCCCGGCUCUGACCCCACCUCCAGCCCUGACUCCGCCACCCCUGAUGAUACCAGCAACUCGUCCUCUGUGGACUGGGACACUGUUGAGAGGCAGGAGGAGGAGGCCCCCAGCUGGGACGAGCUCGCAGUGAUGAUCCCGAGGAGGCCUCGGGAGGGGCCGAGAGCUGACAGCUCCCAAAGGGCUCCGUCUCUCCUCACCAGGUCCCCUGUGGGAGGAGAUGCUGCAGGCCAGAAAAAGGAGGACACCGGCGGUGGGGGCCGGAGCGCAGGACAGCACUGGGCAAGGCUCCGGGGAGAAAGCGGGUUGUCCCUGGAGCGGCACCGGUCAACACUGACCCAGGCUUCCUCCAUGACACCACACAGUGGACCUCGAAGCACCACGUCUCAGGCUUCUCCUGCCCAAAGGGACACUGCUCAGGCUGCCUCUACACGUGAAAUCCCCAGAGCCUCCUCUCCCCAUCGAAUCACCCAAAGGGACACCUCCAGGGCCUCAUCCACCCAACAGGAAAUCUCCAGGGCCUCAUCCACCCAACAGGAAACCUCCAGGGCCUCAUCCACCCAAGAGGACACCCCUAGGGCCUCAUCCACCCAAGAGGACACCCCCAGGGCCUCAUCUACACAGUGGAACACCCCCAGAGCUUCCUCUCCCUCACGAAGCACCCAACUGGAUAACCCCAGAACCUCUUCUACCCAGCAGGACAACCCCCAAACUUCUUUUCCUACUUGUACUCCCCAGCGGGAAAACCCCAGGACACCCUGUGUCCAGCAGGACGAUCCCAGAGCCUCCUCUCCCAACAGAACCACUCAACGAGAGAAUUCCAGAACAUCCUGUGCCCAGCGGGACAAUCCCAAAGCCUCCAGAACCUCCUCUCCCAAUAGAGCCACACGAGACAACCCCAGAACAUCCUGCGCCCAGCGGGACAAUCCCAGAGCCUCCUCUCCCAGUAGAGCUACACGAGACAACCCCACAACAUCCUGUGCCCAGCGGGACAAUCCCAGAGCCUCCAGAACCUCCUCUCCCAAUAGAGCCACACGAGACAACCCCAGAACAUCCUGUGCCCAGCGGGACAAUCCCAGAGCCUCCUCUCCCAGUAGAGCUACACGAGACAACCCCACAACAUCCUGUGCCCAGCGGGACAAUCCCAGAGCCUCCAGAACCUCCUCUCCCAAUAGAGCCACACGAGACAACCCCAGAACAUCCUGCGCCCAGCGGGACAAUCCCAGAGCCUCCUCUCCCAAUAGAGCUGCACGAGACAACCCCACAACAUCCUGUGCCCAGCGGGACAAUCCCAGAGCCUCCAGAACCUCCUCUCCCAAUAGAGCCACACGAGACAACCCCAGAACAUCCUGUGCCCAGCGGGACAAUCCCAGAGCCUCCUCUCCCAAUAGAGCUACACGAGACAACCCCACAACAUCCUGUGCCCAGCGGGACAAUCCCAGAGCCUCCAGAACCUCCUCUCCCAAUAGAGCCACACGAGAUAACCCCAGAACAUCCUGUGCCCAGCGGGACAAUCCCAGAGCCUCCUCUCCCAACAGAACCACCCAACAAGACAGCCCCAGAACAUCCUGUGCCCGACGGGACGAUCCCAGAGCCUCCUCUCCUAACAGAACCAUCCAACAAGAGAACCCCAGAACAUCCUGUGCCCUACGGGACAAUCCCAGAGCCUCCUCUCCCAGCAGAACCAUCCAACAAGAGAACCCCAGAACAUCCUGUGCCCAACGGGACGAUCCCAGAGCCUCCUCUCCUAACAGAACCACCCAACAAGAGAACCCCAGAACAUCCUGUGCCCGACGGGACAAUCCCAGAGCCUCCUCUCGCAACAGAACCAUCCAGCGAGACAACCCCAGAACAUCCUGUGCCCAGCGGGACAAUCCCAGAGCCUCCUCUCCUAACAGAACCAUCCAACAAGAGAACCUCAGAACAUCCUGUACCCGACAGGACAAUCCCAGGACCUCCUCUCCCAAUAGAGCCACACGAGACAACCCCAGAACAUCCUGUGCCCAGCGGGACAAUCUCAGAGCCUCCUCUCCCAUCAGAGCCACCCAACAGGACAACCCCAGAACUUGUAUUCAACAGAACAUCCCCAGAUCAUCUUCUACCCAACAAGACAACCCUAAAACCUCUUGUACCAAACGAGAUAACCUCAGACCCACUUGUACACAGCGGGACCGCACACAGUCCUUUUCCUUUCAACGAGACAACCCUGGAACCUCCUCAUCUCAAUGCUGCACCCAAAAGGAGAAUCUGAGACCAUCAUCUCCCCACCGCUCCACUCAAUGGAACAAUCCCAGGAAUUCAUCUCCCCAUCGUACUAACAAAGACAUCCCCUGGGCCUCGUUUCCCCUCCGGCCAACUCAGAGUGAUGGUCCCCGAACCUCUUCCCCAUCUCGCUCCAAGCAAAGCGAGGUUCCCUGGGCAUCCAUCGCCCUCCGGCCAACCCAAGGUGACAGGCCUCAGACAUCCUCUCCCAGCAGGCCAGCCCAGCAUGACCCACCCCAGUCCUCCUUUGGCCCCACCCAGUACAACUUGCCAUCCCGGGCCACCUCUUCCUCCCAUAACCCAGGCCACCAGAGCACCUCCCGAACUUCCUCACCUGUGUACCCCGCUGCCUAUGGGGCUCCCCUGACCUCUCCUGAGCCCUCCCAGCCUCCAUGUGCUGUGUGCAUUGGGCACCGGGAUGCCCCUCGAGCCUCUUCGCCCCCUCGCUAUUUGCAGCACGACCCCUUCCCCUUCUUCCCAGAGCCCCGCGCCCCUGAGAGUGAACCGCCCCACCACGAGCCUCCCUAUAUACCACCUGCUGUGUGCAUUGGACACCGAGAUGCCCCCCGGGCGUCCUCGCCCCCCCGCCACACCCAAUUUGACCCCUUCCCCUUCCUCCCAGACACAUCAGAUGCCGAGCAUCAGUGUCAGUCCCCCCAACACGAGCCCCUUCAGCUCCCUGCACCUGUGUGUAUUGGGUACCGAGAUGCACCCCGGGCCUCCUCCCCACCACGCCAGGCCCCAGAGCCUUCCCUCUUAUUCCAGGACCUCCCCAGGGCCAGCACAGAGAGCCUUGUCCCUUCCAUGGACUCUCUGCACGAGUGCCCCCACAUCCCCACCCCUGUGUGCAUUGGGCACCGGGAUGCACCCUCCUUCUCAUCCCCACCACGCCAGGCUCCUGAGCCAUCCCUCUUCUUCCAGGAUCCCCCUGGAACUAGUAUGGAGAGCCUGGCCCCCUCCACUGACUCUCUGCAUGGCUCCCCAGUGCUGAUCCCCCAAGUGUGCAUCGGGCACCGGGAUGCACCCCGAGCCUCCUCCCCACCCCGCCACCCACCCAGUGACCUAGCGUUCCUGGCACCCUCACCUUCACCGGGCAGCUCUGGGGGCUCCCGGGGCUCAGCGCCUCCCGGGGAGACCAGGCACAACUUGGAGCGGGAGGAGUACACUGUGCUGGCCGACCUGCCCCCACCCAGGAGGCUGGCCCAGAGACAGCCAGGGCCCCAGGCGCAGUGCAGCAGCGGGGGCCGCACCCACAGCCCUGGCCGUGCAGAGGUGGAGCGCCUCUUCGGGCAAGAGCGCAGGAAGUCCGAGGCAGCGGGGGCCUUCCAGGCCCAGGACGAGGGACGGUCACAGCAGCCCAGCCAAGGCCAGAGCCAACUUCUCCGAAGACAGUCCAGCCCUGCCCCCAGCAGGCAGGUGACCAUGCUCCCUGCCAAACAGGCAGAACUGACCCGGCGGAGCCAAGCAGAGCCCCCUCAUCCUUGGAGUCCUGAGAAGAGACCUGAGGGAGAUCGGCAGCUCCAGGGGUCCCCGCUGCCCCCCAGGACAUCAGCCAGGACCCCUGAGAGGGAGCUGCGGACACAGAGACCUCUGGAGAGUGGCCAAGCAGGCCCAAGACAGCCUCUGGGGGUGUGGCAGAGUCAGGAGGAACCGCCAGGGUCCCAGGGCCCUCAUAGACACCUAGAAAGGAGCUGGAGCAGCCAGGAGGGAGGCCUGGGCCCUGGGGGCUGGUGGGGAUGUGGAGAGCCCAGCCUGGGGGCAGCCAAAGCCCCGGAGGGAGCAUGGGGGGGCACUUCCAGGGAGUACAAGGAGAGCUGGGGGCAGCCAGAGGCCUGGGAGGAGAAGCCCACUCAUGAGCUCCCCAGAGAACUAGGAAAGAGAAGCCCACUCACGAGCCCCCCUGAGAACUGGGGAGGCCCCGCAGAGUCCUCACAAUCCUGGCACUCUGGGACACCCACUGCUGUGGGCUGGGGGGCAGAGGGAGCGUGUCCAUACCCGCGUGGCUCUGAGAGGCGACCCGAGCUUGACUGGAGGGAUCUGCUUGGCCUUCUCCGGGCACCAGGAGAGGGGGUCUGGGCCCGUGUCCCCAGCCUGGACUGGGAGGGCCUCUUGGAGCUCCUGCAGGCCAGGCUGCCCCGCAAGGACCCAGCUGGACACAGGGAUGACCUGGCCAGGGCUUUAGGGCCAGAGCUGGGUCCCCCAGGCACAAACGAUGUCCCUGAGCAGGAGUCACACAGCCAGCCAGAAGGCUGGGCCGAGGCCACCCCAGUCAAUGGACACAGCCCCGCACUGCAGUCCCAGAGCCCGGUCCAGCUGCCCAGCCCUGCCUGCACCUCCACCCAGUGGCCAAAGAUCAAAGUGACAAGAGGACCAGCGACCGCAACUCUGGCAGGCCUGGAGCAGACGGGCCCCCUGGGGAGCAGGAGCACUGCGAAGGGCCCCAGCUUGCCAGAGCUGCAGUUCCAACCAGAGGAGCCUGAGGAGUCAGAACCAAGCAGAGGCCAAGACCCCCUGACUGACCAGAAGCAGGCAGACUCGGCAGACAAGAGGCCAGCAGAGGGCAAGGCUGGGAGCCCGCUCAAGGGCCGACUGGUGACCUCAUGGCGGAUGCCCGGGGACCGGCCCACGCUGUUCAAUCCGUUCCUGCUGUCUCUGGGGGUCCUCAGGUGGCGAAGGCCCGAUCUGCUCAACUUCAAGAAGGGAUGGAUGUCGAUCUUGGACGAGCCUGGAGAGCCUCCCUCCCCCUCGCUCACCACCACCUCUACUUCGCAGUGGAAGAAACAUUGGUUUGUGCUGACAGAUUCAAGUCUCAAAUAUUACAGAGACUCCACUGCUGAGGAGGCAGAUGAGCUGGAUGGUGAGAUCGACCUGCGUUCCUGCACGGAUGUCACUGAGUACGCGGUGCAGCGCAACUAUGGCUUCCAGAUCCACACCAAGGAUGCUGUCUAUACCUUGUCGGCCAUGACCUCAGGCAUCCGGCGGAACUGGAUCGAGGCUCUGAGAAAGACCGUACGUCCAACUUCAGCCCCAGAUGUCACCAAGCUCUCGGACUCUAACAAGGAGAACGCGCUGCACAGCUACAGCACCCAGAAGGGCCCCCUGAAGGCAGGGGAGCAGCGGGCGGGCUCUGAGGUCAUCAGCCGGGGUGGCCCUCGGAAGGCGGACGGGCAGCGUCAGGCCUUGGACUACGUGGAGCUCUCGCCGCUGACCCAGGCUUCCCCGCAGCGGGCCCGCACCCCAGCCCGCACUCCUGACCGCCUGGCCAAGCAGGAGGAGCUGGAGCGGGACCUGGCCCAGCGCUCCGAGGAGCGGCGCAAGUGGUUUGAGGCCACAGACAGCAGGACCCCAGAGGUGCCUGCUGGUGAGGGGCCGCGCCGGGGCCUGGGUGCCCCCCUGACUGAGGACCAGCAAAACCGGCUUAGUGAGGAGAUCGAGAAGAAGUGGCAGGAGCUGGAGAAGCUGCCCCUGCGGGAGAAUAAGCGGGUGCCCCUCACUGCCCUGCUCAACCAAAGCCGCGGAGAGCGCCGAGGGCCCCCAAGUGACGGCCACGAGGCACUGGAGAAGGAGGUUCAGGCUCUUCGGGCCCAGCUGGAGGCGUGGCGUCUCCAAGGGGAGGCUCCUCAGAGUGCACUGAGAUCCCAGGAGGAUGGCCACAUCCCCCCGGGCUACAUCUCACAGGAGGCAUGUGAGCGCAGCCUGGCAGAGAUGGAGUCCUCGCACCAGCAGGUGAUGGAGGAGCUGCAGCGGCACCACGAGCGGGAGCUGCAGCGCCUGCAGCAGGAGAAGGAGUGGCUCCUGGCUGAGGAGACGGCAGCCACGGCCUCAGCCAUUGAAGCCAUGAAGAAGGCCUACCAGGAAGAGCUGAGCCGAGAGCUGAGCAAAACACGGAGUCUCCAGCAGGGCCCGGAUGGCCUCCGGAAGCAGCACCAGUCAGAUGUGGAGGCACUGAAGCGAGAGCUGCAGGUGCUAUCGGAGCAGUACUCGCAGAAGUGCCUGGAGAUUGGGGCACUCAUGCGGCAGGCUGAGGAGCGCGAGCACACGCUGCGCCGCUGCCAGCAGGAGGGCCAGGAGCUGCUGCGCCACAACCAGGAGCUGCAUGGCCGCCUGUCAGAGGAGAUAGACCAGCUGCGCGGCUUCAUUGCCUCGCAGGGCAUGGGCAAUGGCUGCGGGCGCAGCAACGAGCGGAGUUCCUGCGAGCUAGAGGUGCUGCUUCGCGUAAAAGAAAACGAACUCCAGUACCUAAAGAAGGAGGUGCAGUGCCUCCGGGACGAGCUCCAGAUGAUGCAGAAGGACAAGCGCUUCACCUCGGGAAAGUACCAGGACGUCUAUGUGGAGCUGAGCCACAUCAAGACACGGUCUGAGCGGGAGAUCGAGCAGCUGAAGGAGCACCUGCGUCUUGCCAUGGCCGCCCUCCAGGAGAAGGAGUCGAUGCGCAACAGCCUGGCUGAGUAGAGGUCCCGCCCAGCUGCAGACCCUCCAGGCUGGAGGACCAGCCGCCCUCCUUCCCUCCUGGAUGGAAGUAAAAAGCCAAGCUUUCUCCCCACCCUCUGUGGGCCACACGUGCACUUGCACCCACCACACACACACACACACACACACACACACACACAGACACACAGACACAUACGCACACACGUGCACACAUGUACACACGGAUACACACACACACACACACACUGCAUAUCUGAGCGCGCCCCUCGCACUGGGUCUCACCUUGCACCUUCUUCAGGAUUUUAUAUGUGAAGAGAUUUUUAUAUAGAUUUUUUUCCUUUUUUUCCAAAACACUUUAUACUUUAAAAAAAAAAAAAAAAAGCAAUUCCUGGUGGCUGUGUGCCUCCAACCCUGGUCCCCCUCUGUCUCCAGCCACCCUCUGCUUGGGCUUCUGAGCUGGUGGCCCUGGCCCAGAGGUCUGGCGGAGGCCCAGGCAGCAGCCAUGGCGGGGUGUCUCUACAGGGGAGAGGCGGGAGCCUGCCACCCUCUUCCUGCCCUACCUCCUACUAACACUUCCUGCCCCAUUUGGACCCGUACCAUGGGGCUCAGGACAGAGGGAGCUAGCAGCUGGCCUCCAUGGCCCCACAGCCUCCUUCGAGGCUGUGCUGGGUGCAGAACCGCCAGAGCCACCCAAAAGGUGUUUCUCUUCUGCUCCCUGAACCUCUUAACUUAAUAAAACGUUCCAGCAGCUCUGGUGUCCUAGAUGGCUGGCAGAACAGGAAUGGAGAUUGGGGUUUCUUGAAGUGGCUUCCCCACUCACACCCUACCCACACCCCACCCUUCCUAAAGCAGCGGCCUCUAGGCUUCUGAGGGUGGGGCUGAAAAUCCAAGGUCUCCCUUAGUACAGACUGUGACGCCCCCAGUGUGGCUUGCAGGCUAGUGGCAGCGGAAGCAUGUGGGAAAUAGCAAGUCCAGUCCCACCCCAACCUACUGAACCAGCGUCUGCAUUUUAACAGGGUGCCCCAGUGAUUCACGUGACCUUCAAAGUCUGAGGAGCCCUGGAGUAGGGCCCAGGGCCCAGGCCUGAGAGAGAGGCCUGGGGCUAAGACUAGCCCUGACCAUGACCUUGGGCAAGUCACACCCCUCACUGAGCCUCAGUUUGCUUCUCCAUCAAAUGGGUGUUUUUCUUUCAGUCCCAGUCCUCUCCUGAGGCUUUUCCCAGAGGUCAUGCCCAGCCCUGGGCAGGGGUGAGGGCAGGGUUGUGGCUGCCAGGCACAGGUCCAGCGGGCUGGGAGUCCUCACCAUGGCUGGCUGUGCUGAUUAUGGUUGCAUGGGGCUGGGAAGAGGUCCCAUUUCUGAGCCACAGAAACAGGCCACAUCCAGUAGGGGUCCUGGAAGGCUGUGAGAACCCAGAGGAGACCCUGACCCAGCCUGCAGGUAGAAGACUGCCUUUGGAGGCAGCUUUGAAAGAUGACUCUUCCAGAUGGAAGAAUCAGGAAGGGCCUUCCCACGUGGAGGCACCAGCAGGAGCAAACGUCCCUGGUGUGUUCAGGCAAAGAGCCACAGGAGAGUGACCUCGUGGAGUGGGAAGAGAUUGUUUCCCAUUCCCUUGCCAGGGAUUGGUUGAGGAAUGGACAAGGCUUGCAGUUCACGCAAGCCAGUGAAAUGCGAGGGGAAGUCUUGGGAGUGGGGUGGAGGAGGUCAUCUGGGAAGGGUGUCCUUGGUCUUAAAAAGAGGCACAAGAGGCCGGGCGCGGUGGCUCUUGCCUAUUAUCCUAGCACUUUGGGAGGCCAAGGCAGGGGGAUCACUUGAGGUCAGGAGUUCGAGACCAGCCUGGCCAACAUGGUGAAACCCCGUCUCUACUAAAAAUACAAAAAAUUAGCCAGACGUGGUGCCAAGCACCUGUAAUCCCAGCUACUCAGGAGGCUGAGGCAGGAGAAUCACUUGAACCCAGGAGGCAGAAGUUGCAGUGAGCCAAGAUCGCGCCACUGCACUCCAGCCUGUGUGACAAGGGCGAAACUCCAUCUCAAAAAAAAAGGGGGAGGGUGGCGCAAGGAGAGGACACCUCUCUCCUGGCCCUGUCGCCAUCUUCCCUCAUCAAUAGCUAAAAAUGGCAAAGAAGAAAGAGCCAGGACCCCGUGCCAUCAAAUCCUCCGGCCUUGUGCUGCCCUGUCUCGGCACUGCUUGCCUUAGGAGAUCAGGAGUGUUCCUAGCCACUGGGAGAUGGGAUGCCUGCCACUGGCAGCUCUGCCGUCCAUCCUCACCAUCCCACCGUCCCCCCAAGACAGCUCUCCAUCCCAUCCUCUGCCUCCCUUCUAGCCUCAACCUAACUCAGGGCUCCCCCGUCUCACACCUGGGUUGCAGGAACAUCCUCUUCACCAACCCCCCUCCCAUCCCUCCUCAGGGCUGCCUAGGGCAGCUACAAAAACCAGGCCAGCCUCUGAAAGGUGCUCCACAUCUCAUUAAAAACCGUGAAAUCGCACUGCCCCACUAUCAGAAUAGCUCAGAGGAGAAGGUCUGCCAGUACCAAGUGCUGGUGGGGAUACGGAGAAGAGCAGCUCCCAGGCGCUGCUGGUGCAAAUGUGCUUUGUUGCACCCACGGCAGGAAACUGACCAGCUUCUCAUCAAGUUAAAUACGCAUCUACCCUAUGGCCUAGCAUUUCCACUCUUGCUUACACAUCCAGGAGAAAUGAGUCCUUACAUGCACAAAAGGAUGAGUACCGUAAUACUCACAUCAGCAAAUAAACAAUACAGCUGUGUGUCAGUAGUAGAAUGAAUAAAUUGUGGUCGAUUCAUA